AGGGUAGGUCAUGCUGGCAACAGGAAGCAACUUCUUAGCCAGGGCCGGGGGGCGGGUGUCUGGCUGGAAUCUCCCCUGGGUACAUGGAGGGUGCCAGCCGGCUGGACCUGCAGACCCAGGAAGCUGGAACAUAGGCAUGGGGUGCAGGGGGCAUUAGGCUAGGGUCCAGGGAGGGGCCACAGACCUGCCUCCUGCAAGCCCACAGAGCCUGCUCCCCGAGCCUCUCUCUGCUGGCCUCCCUGCCCUGCCCACACCCCCACUCCACCACAGGAGAAGACGUCCUGCCUCAGAGGCCUGCUUCCCAGUGCGAGCACUUGUGCCCUGGGUCAGGACCUCUGGCUGGAGACCUGACUCCUGGUGGAGGGAAGGCGGCCUGCCUGCCAAGCAGCCUGCCCACCCUGGGAGCUAGAACUGGGGUUCUCGUGGUUCCUGCAGUCCCGUCAUCCAGAGGAGGCCGGUAGCUGAGAGCAGUCCUAAGCAGGCUCCUUCCGCCCCCACCCCUCCAGCAGCUCUGUUCUUGCCUUGGCAGAGCCAGCCCCCACCAGCGGCAGCCCCCAGGACUCCCUCCUUCCCCAAACCAGAGAGCCUCUGGCUCGGACAGAUGCCAUUUGUCAAUGUCCUUGCAAACACGUGGUGCCCAGAAACCAGGGUGGGCGGCUUGGCCGGGCCACCCCAGACAGGAGGUCUGCGGGAAUAUCCCAUUUAGCAUAGCUCAGCGAAAACUGCUCCCACCUUCCGGCCAAUCUACCUCUGAUGAUGCAGCCUCGGCUUUCCCAAGCCUCUUGGCCGCCACCCCUCACCGCUGGCUCGCAGCGGACGCGCCUGUGGUUGAGCCGGCGACAACAGGGCGCCCCUCACGUGUCUGGGGGCAGCCGCUCUUCCAGCCCUGGGCUUGGCCAGCAGCUGGCCAGGGGCAUGCCUGUCACUUGGGGCUCACCCGCGUCUCCGUCUCCCACCCCAGCCCACACGGUGUUGCGGCCUGACCCAGGCUGUGUACUUGGGGCCUGCUUUGUGCUGGGGUGGCAUGGAGGACAGAGCCCUGGAGGCAGGUUCUAGCCCCAUCCCUGGAGGGACUCGGCCUCUGUGGCCUCAUUUCUACACUAGGGUGAUGGUGGGGCCACCCCAAAGUCCCCAAGGCACAGUCGAGCUCAGCAUGUCCCUGGCAGGUUCUGGGUGCUCAGGAAGCAGAAUACUCAGGCCUCCACACCCCUGGCCCCAGGUCCUCCUUGGACCACAGGAGACACAGGCCUCCCACCUCAGGAGGGAGGAGGGCUGGCCUGACCACUGUCCCUCCCACCCUAGGACACAGUCAUGCUCAUAUCGGCUGCGUCGAUGGCACCCGAGGUGUGCGGCCCAAGCCUCCAGGGAACCCCUGGACCCCCACCGCCCCUGCUGCCCAAGCCAGGGAAGGACAACUUGCGUUUGCAGAAGCUCCUGAGGAAGGCAGCCCGGAAGAAGAUGAUGGGAGGCACACACCUCGCUCCACCCAGGGCCUUCCGCACCUCCCUGUCCCCCGUGAGUGAGGCCAGCCAUGACCAGGAGGUCACAGCCCCGCACGCUGCUGAGGGCCCGCACCCCGCCGAAGCCCCACGCCUUCCUGAAGCCCCACGCCCCGCCGAGGCUCCCCGCAUGGUGGCUGCCCUACCCCGCUCCCCGCACACCCCCAUCAUCCACCACGUGGCAUCACCCCUGCAGAAGUCCACGUUCUCCAUCGGCCUCACCCAGCGCAGGAUUCUAGCUGCUCAAUUCAGGGCCAUGGGGCCCCAGGUUGUAGCCUCGGCCCCAGAACCUACCCGGCCCCCCAGUGGCUUCGUCCCUGUCUCUGGGGGUGGGGGCACCCACGUCACCCAGGUGCACAUCCAGCUGGCACCAUCCCCACACAAUGGGACCCCUGAGCCUCCCAGGACAGCCCCAGAAGUGGGAUCCAACAGCCAGGAUGGAGAUGCCACCCCAAGUCCCCCCAGGGCCCAGCCCCUGGUCCCAGUGGCUCACAUCCGCCCACUGCCCACCACAGUCCAGGCUGCCAGUCCCUUGCCUGAGGAGCCCCCUGUACCACGGCCGCCACCCGGCUUCCAGGCCUCAGUGCCCAGAGAGGCUAGUGCCAGGGUUGUGGUGCCCAUAGCCCCGACCUGCCGCUCGCUGGAGUCCUCACCGCACAGCCUGGUCCCCAUGGGCCCUGGCAGAGAGCACCUGGAGGAGCCCCCGAUGGCUGGCCCCGCCGCUGAGGCCGAGCGAGUGUCCAGCCCUGCCUGGGCCUCAUCCCCUACCCCACCAUCAGGCCCUCACCCAUGCCCUGUCCCCAAAGUUGCACCCAAGCCCCGGCUCAGUGGCUGGACGUGGCUCAAGAAGCAGCUGCUGGAGGAGGCCCCAGAGCCUCCGUGCCCAGAGCCGCGGCAGAGCCUGGAGCCAGAGGUGCCCACCCCCACAGAGCAGGAGGUGCCUGCCCCCACAGAGCAGGAGGUGCCCGCCCUCACCGCACCCCGGGCCCCCGCCUCCCGGACCUCCAGGAUGUGGGAUGCCGUGCUGUACCGCAUGUCAGUGGCGGAGGCCCAAGGGCGCCUGGCAGGGCCCAGCGGUGGGGAGCACACCCCAGCCAGCCUCACCCGCCUGCCCUUCCUGUACCGGCCUCGCUUCAACGCCCGGAAGCUGCAGGAGGCCACCCGGCCCCCUCCCACAGUCCGCUCCAUCCUGGAGCUGAGCCCCCAGCCCAAGAACUUCAACCGCACAGCGACUGGCUGGAGGCUCCAGUGAAGUGGCCAGAAUGGCCCCCAGAGCCCAGGACCAUGGGAUGGACAGAAGAAGGGGCUGAGGCUCUAGCUGGGGGCCCAUAGUUGCUGCAUGAAGAUGCACCAGGGCCCAAGGGGCAUGGGGUGCAGGGCAGCCUGGGAAGGGCACAUGGGGUGCUGAGGGAAGUCUGCAUGGUUAGGAGGGUGGUCAGGUGGACGGGGCAGAGAGGACGAGCUGGAGCCCCUGGGCUGCAGUGGUGUGAGGGGAACAGAGAAGGGGUCUGCGUCGGGAUGUAGGAUGGGGGCCUUGGGAUGAAAACUUUAGGUAAGAUGGCAGAGGACUGCAUCUACUGACCUAGCCCAGGCUCCUCAGGGGCCUGGGCCUCUCACUGAUCCUCCCUUUUGCUGUCACCUUUUGCUGUCAAAGGUUUGGGGCCAGAUCUCUGCUUGCUGAGGCAUGGGUGCGGUCAGGCUGGCUUGGCCAUCGGCGUCAGGAGCAGUCAGCAGUUUUGCUGCCUGUGCUUCCUGAUGGCAGAGCCAGAUCCUGGGACUAGGGUGCAGGGGGGAGCCCUCAGCCAGCGUGGGACUUGGCACCAAUACAAGUGCUCAGGGGCAGGCAGGGAGGGGCUCAUCAGGGGUGGAGGAGGGCCCAGCGUGACCUCUCUCUCGGCCCACCUCUGCUUCCCCUACCUGGGCUGACAGCCUGAGGGGGCAGAACUCGAGGGAUUCGCUGGUGGGACAGCGAGGGUCUCAGCACUGGCCAUGCCCAGGCUUUGACAGCUGGAUGAGGAGGGAGCCCUCAGUCCCAACCCUAUGGGAACAGCUUGGCCAAGCGGGACAGAGAAGGGGCUGUGGCCCUGGUGGGGAGAGUGGAGGGGCCUACUCAGCAGUCAGCCAGGCUCUGGUGGGGGUGGCCAACCACAGGAGAGGGACACAGAGGUACCAGAAAAAGCCUCUGCCACAGCUGCUUGAGAGUCAGGGUUUGGCAGGGGAAGAUGGUAGGAGGACAGCUGCCCCACCCUGUGGUGUGAUGGGUGCUGGAAAUGGAGCCUGGGGCCCAGGUCACUAAUAAAUGUGUGUCUCACCAUGGCA